ACUGGGGGGUGUGAGGAACAGGGGGGACCAUGGACUUCAUCAGCAUUCAGCAGUUGGUAAGUGGAGAAAGAGUUGAAGGGAAAGUGUUGGGAUUUGGACAUGGAGUUCCUGACCCUGGAGCCUGGCCUAGUGACUGGAGGAGGGGCCCCCAAGAGGCUGUGGCCCGGGAGAAGCUGAAAUUGGAAGAAGAGAAGAAGAAGAAACUUGAAAGAUUUAACAGUACCAGAUUUAAUCUGGAUAACCUGGCUGACUUGGAAAACUUGGUUCAAAGACGGAAAAAGCGACUGAGACACAGAGUCCCCCCCAGGAAACCUGAGCCCCUGGUUAAGCCGCAGUCCCAGGCCCAGGUGGAGCCUGUGGGCCUGGAGAUGUUCCUGAAGGCAGCUGCUGAGAACCAGGAGUACCUGAUUGACAAGUACUUGACAGACGGAGGGGACCCCAAUGCCCAUGACAAGCUCCACCGCACCGCCUUGCACUGGGCCUGUCUGAAGGGUCACAGCCAGCUGGUGAACAAGCUGCUGGUGGCAGGUGCCACAGUGGACGCGCGAGACUUGCUGGACAGGACACCUGUGUUCUGGGCCUGCCGCGGAGGACAUCUGGUCAUCCUCAAACAGCUGCUUAACCAGGGAGCCCGGGUCAAUGCCCGGGACAAGAUCGGGAGCACCCCCCUGCACGUGGCAGUGCGCACCCGGCACCCCGACUGCCUGGAGCACCUCAUCGAGUGUGGCGCCCACCUGAACGCACAGGAUAAGGAAGGGGACACGGCUCUGCACGAGGCCGUGCGGCACGGCAGCUACAAAGCCAUGAAGCUACUGCUGCUCUAUGGGGCCGAGCUGGGGGUGCGGAACGCGGCCUCCGUGACCCCGGUGCAGCUGGCUCGAGACUGGCAGCGCGGCAUCCGGGAGGCCCUGCAGGCCCACGUGGCGCAUCCCCGCACCCGGUGCUGACCGCAGCACCGCCCCCCGCCGCGCCUUUCGCACUGCCACCAUUCCAUCCUGUGCCCCGCCCCCGCGUCUGCACCUCUGUGGUUCCUGCCCUCAGCCCUGGUUCCUCCCUCUCUGGCCUGUGCCGCCUCAGCAGCCCUGGCAGAACUGAAGAGCGGCACCGGGCCCAGCAGGCAAAGAGAGAGGCCUCCCUGGCUUCGAGUGUCAGGGGAGCCGCGUUCCCUCCCAGGGCUGGAGCAGAGGACCACAAGGCAGCAGAAAGCGCGGGUCCAGAUGAGGGCCAGGAAGGGGAGGAGAGUGAGGGCCAAGAACGAGCCUUAAGGGAGCAGUCCCAAGCUGGAGCCACCCAGGGCUGGGUCUGGGAGUCCUCAGUGUCCACUUGUCCCAGGUUAGGGGGCUUGCCUUGCUCUCUCCAGGGCCAGUCUGUGUGUGUGGGGACUCAGCCCGUGGCCGGCAGAUGCCAUCCAGGAUGUACAAGGUGCAGCCAAGGCAGGCCAUGCAGGGGCCGGGCCUGUCUGCAGCUGGUGGAUGCCUGUGGGCAUGGCUUUCUCUGGGGACCCCAUUCCUGUCAGUAGCAACCCUGGCAGUGUCCGGAGCGGCUCUAGACAACUUUGGUCAUAGGAACUCUGGAGGUGGGUUCUGGUCAUCUGAGGUGGCUACUCAACAGGUUUGAGGCCCCACAGCAACAGAAGUCCAGGACCCACUAGGUUGCCUCAGAAGCCCUAAGACUGAUGAGCUGGAGCGCGCAUUUGAGAGAAGCCUCGCACCCACUGUGUACUGGCCCCGCUCAGGCCGGCCUGGCACACCGUUGCCUGCUGGCGGCUCUCAUGGGGAAGCGCCUGGGCACUGGGGAUUGCUUGUGGCCCACUCAACUCUUGGGGCAGUGGCCCGUAACCCUAGUUUGCCUGAGGCCCUUAUGUCCCCUUAUGUUCCUGGUACUGGAGCUUGAGCUCUUGCCUGGAACGCUGCAGCUGCACCCACCCUGCUUGAUCCCACCUGGGAGGCCAGGACACUGAGGAGCUCUGAACCCAGCCCACAGGGAAGCAGAGGAAGGUGAGCCCCCGCCGCCCCCCAGCCCUUCCCAUCCCUUCCCUGCUCCCUGGUGGUCUAAGGACCCAAGCUCCCUAGACUUCCUCUUCCACCGUCUGUACGUUUCAAAUUACACUGGUGUAGGCCUGUACUGCUGGUGGGGCUGGGCCCCUAAACGCCAGAAAGUGAAUCUUAAGAAGCUCUGCCCUAAACUGAGAACCACAUGCUGAGGGAAGGGCUGAAAGGUGAAGGCUCAGCCUCCCUCACAUGGGUCCUGGGUUACAUUAGGUACCGGGCUGAUUGAUAGGCAUUUGGCCAUGGUUCCUUUUCGUCUACCUUUGGGGGCCUUCUCAGGCCCAGAACAAGGCUGUUGUUACUAUGUGGAAAAGCUGACCAGUGCUGCACACUAGGGGCACACACCUUUCCAUGAGCAGCUCCUGCCCUGUGGCGACAGCCAGCGUGCACCCAGACGCUGGUGCCAUGGCGAAGCAGGCGUUCAAGACCAUGGAGAAGACAACUCCUCAUCUAGAAAAUGAGGACACCUCAGUGACAAACACACCUUUUUAUACCAAUCAGUAUCCUCUGUUCAUUAAAACUGGCUAUCCAUUACA